UGCCUGGCCUCCUGCCAGCAACAAGCAGGAGCUGAAAACCAGAAGUUGAGGCGUGAGUUUGGCCACUCCGUAGUGUGCACUUGGUGAGGGCAGCAGCUCGCCACAGCUGCCAGCCAUCUGUCCAUUCACCCAUCUGUCCAUCUGGCAGCCCGCUGUUCAGACCUGUCUGUCUGUCCGCCCAUCUGUAAGCCCAUCUCUGUCCCAUUGUCUAUCUGACCAUCUUUCUCUUACUGUCCUCUUUGUCUAGCUAUCUGGCCUAUCUGUCGAUCCAUCUUCGUGUCUGUCUUCAGCCCCCACCUGUUUGUCCAUCUGUCCAAUUACCUGUGACUCUGUGCAUCUUCUUGUCCAUUCAUCUGCCCACCCAUCCGUCCCUCCGUCUGCCCACCAGCCGCCCCUCUCCUCCUGGGCUGCAGAGCCAUGGCCCGGGGCUACGGGGCCACGGUCAGCCUAGUCCUGCUGGGUCUGGGGCUGGCGCUGGCUGUCAUUGUGCUGGCUGUGGUCCUCUCUCGACACCAGGCCCCAUGUGGCCCCCAGGCCUUUGCCCACGCUGCUGUUGCCGCCGACUCCAAGGUCUGCUCGGAUAUUGGACGAGCCAUCCUCCAGCAGCAGGGCUCACCCGUGGAUGCCACCAUCGCGGCUCUGGUCUGCACCAGCGUCGUCAACCCUCAGAGCAUGGGCCUGGGCGGAGGGGUCAUCUUCACCAUCUACAAUGUGACAACAGGGAAGGUGGAGGUCAUCAAUGCCCGGGAGACGGUGCCGGCCAGCCACGCCCCGAGCCUGCUGGACCAGUGUGCACAGGCUCUGCCACUGGGCACAGGGGCCCAGUGGAUCGGGGUGCCCGGGGAGCUCCGUGGCUAUGCCGAGGCCCACCGCCGCCAUGGCCGCCUGCCCUGGGCGCAGCUGUUCCAGCCCACCAUCGCGCUGCUCCGAGGGGGGCAUGUGGUGGCCCCUGUCCUCAGCCGUUUCCUGCACAACAGCAUCCUGCGGCCUUCCUUGCAGGCGUCAACCCUGCGCCAGCUCUUCUUCAACGGGACAGAACCCCUGAGGCCUCAGGACCCACUCCCAUGGCCUGCACUGGCCACCACCCUGGAGACCGUGGCCACAGAGGGCGUGGAGGUCUUCUACACGGGGAGGCUGGGCCAGAUGCUGGUGGAGGACAUUGCCAAGGAAGGGAGCCAGCUGACGCUGCAGGACCUGGCCAAGUUCCAGCCCGAGGUGGUGGAUGCCCUGGAGGUGCCCCUGGGGGACUAUACCCUGUACUCACCACCGCCGCCUGCAGGGGGUGCCAUUCUCAGCUUUAUCCUCAACGUGCUAAGAGGGUUCAACUUCUCAACAGAGUCUAUGGCCAGGCCUGAAGGGAGGGUGAACGUGUACCACCACCUUGUAGAGACGCUCAAGUUUGCCAAGGGGCAGAGGUGGAGGCUGGGGGACCCUCGAAGCCACCCGAAGCUCCAGAAUGCCUCCCGGGACCUGCUGGGGGAGACCCUGGCCCAGCUCAUCCGCCAACAGAUCGAUGGCCGGGGGGACCACCAGCUCAGCCACUACAGCUUGGCCGAGGCCUGGGGCCACGGGACAGGCACGUCCCAUGUGUCUGUGCUGGGGGAGGAUGGCAGCGCCGUGGCUGCCACCAGCACCAUCAACACACCCUUUGGAGCGAUGGUGUAUUCACCACGGACAGGCAUCAUCCUCAACAACGAGCUCCUGGACUUAUGCGAGCGAUGCCCCCGGGGUUCCGGCACCACCCCCUCACCUGUGAGUGGAGACAGGGUGGGUGGAGCUCCCGGAAGGUGCUGGCCCCCAGUUCCAGGCGAGCGUUCCCCAUCCUCCAUGGUGCCCUCCAUCUUGAUCAACAAAGCCCAGGGGUCGAAGCUAGUGAUUGGCGGGGCUGGCGGGGAGCUCAUCAUCUCUGCUGUGGCCCAGGCCAUCAUGAGCAAGCUGUGGCUUGGCUUUGACCUGAGAGCGGCCAUUGCAGCCCCCAUCCUGCAUGUCAACAGCAAGGGCUGUGUGGAGUACGAGCCCAACUUCAGCCAGAGACGGUGUCUUGCUUUGUUGCCCUGGCUGUUCUCAAACUCCUGGCCUCAAGUGAUCCUGCCACCUUGGCUCCCAAGUGGCUAAGACUGUAGGUGUGAACCACUGUGUCUGGCCUCAGUGUCUAAAUCUUGAGAAGCCACAUCCUCCAUCGAAGGCCCCCUGAACUCAGAUUUGCACCUCAAGGCCCUGGUGUCCUUGGAUCCAGAACAGACAUGAACUUGCAUUUGGAGGUCUUCGGGCCUGGGUGGUGUCCUUCGUACAUAGUCCCUGGAGGCUGAGCUUGUCCUCUAUGGGCCUUUGGAUCUCUUCCAUGCUCCCAUCUGGUCCUCCCCUCUUCCUGUGUCUUCAGGCCCUCUUCCUCUCCGUCUUGCCUUUUGAUCAUUUUUCUCAUUUCUUGCAGAGGCCUCUCCCUCCUGGAGAUGGGCUGAGCUGCCCUCCCCUGUGAACCUGCUUUCUCUCCUCUCCAGGAGGUGCAGAGGGGACUCCAAGACCGUGGCCAGAACCAGACCCAGAGGCCCUUCUUCCUGAACGUGGUCCAGGCUGUGUCCCAGGAGGGGGCCUGUGUGUACGCCGUCUCGGACCUGAGGAAGAGUGGGGAGGCCGCAGGCUACUAAGACACUGCUCUGCCCAGAGCUGAAGUCUGGCCCCACCAUGAGUCCUGUGUCCAGGCCGGACAUGGCUGGGGGACCAACUACUCUGGCAGGAUCUGGACCCCUGGCAGGGGAGUCCAGCUGAGAGUGGAAGAGGUGGCGGGGACCAGCUGGGCAGAUGAGAGGCUGAGCCUCAUCCCUAACCCCCUUUCCCAGAGCCCCUGGUGGUCCUGAACCGGCCCCUCUAUCCCUCCGCAGGCCUCUUGCCUGGGGCCACUCUCCCACCCUCUCGAUCUGUAUAUCCUCCAGUCCAAGAUUAAAGAGGCGGACUGUG